AGUGGCGUUUCCGACUGUGGGAGCCUCAGCUUCCCAGUCGUCCGAUGAGCCCGAGCAGCUGAGUCCCUUCCCUGUCUUUCACUCUUCUGGCAUCGGUGGUUUUACUUCUUCGAUUGAACCCUGCUUCCUCGACCCCCCUGGGAGGCCGCCUUCUUCAGGCGCCUCCCUUCUCUCCACGAGCUCGCUCUGACAGCUGAGGAACUGGCAAGAUCCUGCUACCCAGAGGGUGAAUGGGUAUCUUUCCCGGAAUAAUCCUAAUUUUUCUAAGGGUGAAGUUUGCAACGGCGGCCGUGAUUCACCAGAAAAGUACCACUGUAAGUCAUGAGAUGUCUGGUCUGAAUUGGAAACCCUUUGUAUAUGGCGGCCUUGCCUCUAUCGUGGCUGAGUUUGGGACUUUCCCUGUGGACCUUACCAAAACACGACUUCAGGUUCAAGGCCAAAGCAUUGAUGCCCGUUUCAAAGAGAUAAAAUAUAGAGGGAUGUUCCAUGCGCUGUUUCGCAUCUGUAAAGAGGAAGGUGUAUUGGCUCUCUAUUCAGGAAUUGCUCCUGCGUUGCUAAGACAAGCAUCAUAUGGCACCAUUAAAAUUGGGAUUUACCAAAGCUUGAAGCGCUUAUUCGUAGAACGUUUAGAAGAUGAAACUCUUUUAAUUAAUAUGAUCUGUGGGGUAGUGUCAGGAGUGAUAUCUUCCACUAUAGCCAAUCCCACCGAUGUUCUAAAGAUUCGAAUGCAGGCUCAAGGAAGCUUGUUCCAAGGGAGCAUGAUUGGAAGCUUUAUCGAUAUAUACCAACAAGAAGGCACCAGGGGUCUGUGGAGGUGCUUAUGUUCAAAAGCUGUUACCGGCUGUGUGCUGUGGCUCAUGCCUGUAAUCCCAGCACUUUGGGAGGCCAACGCGGGUGGAUCACUUGAGGGUGUGGUUCCAACUGCUCAGCGUGCUGCCAUCGUUGUAGGAGUAGAGCUACCAGUCUAUGAUAUUACUAAGAAGCAUUUAAUAUUGUCAGGAAUGAUGGGCGAUACAAUUUUAACUCACUUCGUUUCCAGCUUUACAUGUGGUUUGGCUGGGGCUCUGGCCUCCAACCCGGUUGAUGUGGUUCGAACUCGCAUGAUGAACCAGAGGGCAAUCGUGGGACAUGUGGAUCUCUAUAAGGGCACUGUUGAUGGUAUUUUAAAGAUGUGGAAACAUGAGGGCUUUUUUGCACUCUAUAAAGGAUUUUGGCCAAACUGGCUUCGGCUUGGACCCUGGAACAUCAUUUUUUUUAUUACAUACGAGCAGCUAAAGAGGCUUCAAAUCUAAGAACUGAAUUAUAUGUGAGCCCAGCCCUGCCAGCCUUUCUACUCCUUUGCCCUUUUCCCGUGUUCUAAUGUAUUUUGACAAUGUUGUAAGUGUUUACCAAGCCGUUGGUCUCCUAAGGGCCUCCUGAUGGAAGAACAGUGGGGUGGUUCAAAGUUAUUUCUAUGUUUGUGUUACCAUGUUAACUUUUCCCCGAGAGAAAGUGUUAACAUUGAGACUCUGGCCCCAGAUUGGUAUCUUCUAUGAAGAUGGAUACUGAUGGGUGACAUUGAAAACGGCCUGCUUUCCAAAUGUGGUUAAAUGUAAUUGGUUAGCCCCAGACUUGGGCUAGAGCAGAAGGCAUAGGCCAGGGUGGUUAUUGCUAUAUGUGUUACAGACCUCGGUUCUCAUUAAAGUAUUUAUUGGCAGAA